CGGACACGGGGCGGGGCCUCAGCGCGGCGGGGCGGGGCUGCCCUGAGGCCCCACCCCGCUUCGGCGCCGGGAACAAAGGCGCCCGCGCACCCGUGGGGAGGACCCCCGCCCGUCGGCCCGCCGCGCCUGCGCCCCGCGACCCCCAGACAGGCCGCAGGCGGGGACGGAGGCGCGAUGGCGGCGGGAGCGCGCGCCGUUCCCGGUCGACCCACCCAGCCCUCAGUCCCGCAGAGCUUUCUCACGCGGCCCCGGACACAGCCCGGCGGCCACGAGCGGCCCUGUCACGCACGGCAGCCCCGCCCACAGGCCGCAGGCCCGGCGGCCGGCGCGUCAGUCAGGCGUACUCGCACGGGCGGCCGCUACCCCGCGGUCCCGCACAGACGCAGCCCCCGCGUCCCGAACACCGCCCAUGCAGCGACCGGGACGGGACGUGAGGGGAUGGCGCGUCCUCCGGGAAUGCCCGGCCAAACUCAGUUACCUGGGCGGGCUUCCCGGACAAGGGAGCCAGGACGGGCCGCCUCACACCGGCGGCGGCGGGUCCUCCGCGCGCCCUCUCCCGGGAGGGGCGGGGGCGGGGCUGCCUGCGGAUUGGUCGCGGGCACUGAUGGACAGCCGACAUGUCCCGCCCCCCCGGCAGCGCGGGGCUGGUCCGCAGGCAGUUCUGGCGACGGCCAGACCCACGUCUGUCUGUUCCGCCCCUGCUGCCAGGGUGGCUUUCAGUGGUCCUCUCUUUCGGAGAGUUCCCCCCAAGCGUGAGCACCCCUUACAGGGGCGUUAGGUCCGCGGCCGCGCUGUCCAGUGGUCUGACCUGCAGCUCCCAGGGCCUUUGUGUCUGUCCCUCGCAUGGGCCUCUGCACGCUCCGUCCCCACGCGACAGGACUCGAGUCCGAUUCGGGGCUCCGACUCAGACCCUACCCCGCAGCGCCCUCCUGCAAAUGCUCUCCUGAACUUUGGUUUUCCCCGCCUUGCUUUCUUCCUCCUCCUGUAGCCGCUGCCUCUCGAUCUCAGAAGCUUCUCUUCCUCUGCACUCAGUGCUAGGCCAGAUCCCAAGGCGACCUGACCUUUCCCCUGGCUUUGCCCAACAACACAGGCACCGGUGACUCCAAACCUGCAUCUCCCCUACGUUCCAGGCCCCAGCAUCCCACUGCAUGUUCCACAUCCCCCCCCCUUAGACAGCUCGCCUUCCCUCCCCAAACGAUUCCUUCCACAGUCUUCACUUUCUCAGAACGCGGCGCUAAACUUCUCUAAGUUGGAAGGUCAAAAACCUUGCAGCUAACUUUGAUUCCUCCCUUUGCCUCACCUCCAAUCCAUCAAGACCUUGUCACUCAGCCCACAAGCUGAAGGCCCCAUCUCCUGUCACCCAGACUACUCACCUUGUUUGGUUUUGCCUGGAUCUAUCAGUUUGGUUUUGCCUGGAUUUAUCAUGCUUUAAAUCUUUAAAAUGAAAUUAAAUCAUGAUCCCCUACAUCCAGGCUAAAACCCUCCGUGAAUUCCCAUUGCACCUAAAAUCCACACUCCCUGCUUGGCCUAGCAGGUUCUAUAUGACCUGCCCAUCUCACCAGUUUCAUCUCUCACAAGUGAUCCUUCACUCUCCAUUCUCCAGCCACAAGGCCUUUUUCUGGUUAUGGAAUAUAAUUCAUACUCUUUGUCUUUCUGAAGCCAUUCUUGAAACUCACCCCUGCAAUCUAUCUACCCUUGUCAGCACCGCCAAAAUUGAGGACACCCACGGUCGCGGUGGAGCCUGUCUGACAUGUUGAGCCAGGCAGUGGGUCGGCUGCCAGGCACAGCAGGACAACUUACUGCAUUUCAGAGGAAUGAUGGUCCACAAUUUACUGAUGAGGAAACAGAGAUUCAGAGAAGUUCUACAAUUUGCCCCAAAGCCACAUAACAUGACUAGGUGGGAACUAGAACCCAAGUCGGCCUGACUCCAUGAGUUUUCUGCCUCACAGGAGAUCCACUGGCUUAGGUAAGUCCUGGUGGUCAGUAGUCAGUGGGCAUGGAGGCUAUCUGGUUAAUCAGCAUGGGUGAGGGGAGGCAUGCUCACCGCUGGCCUUGGGCACAGGGAAUCCAGCAGAACGUGAGUGCUCACAGAGUGUGGCUUGAACUGGCUUAGGCUUGAAGUUCUGUGGACCCUGCUCUUCUCUGUGUUGGGCAUUGACAACAUGAGGAGCACAAGAGAGACACAGCGCCAGCUCUCUGGGAGUUCAGACAUUAAAUAAACACUCUGUUACAUAAAGACAAUUAUGAUGAGGGCUAGAAGGAAAAACAUUGGGUCGAGAUCUCUUCAGACCUCAGCAGAGGUCUAAAGGAAGUGAGUCGAUGGCGAGGUGAAUUAUUAAAGGUGGGUUGGAGAAAAGUACAUUCCAAGUAGAGGUAACAGCAUGUACAAAGGCCCUGAGGCCAGGAAGAGGUUGUUGAAUUUAGGGUUACAAAGCUAGAGUUUCCUGACUGAGGAGGGGACAGGGAGUGAUGAGACCAGGAAGGCAGACGGGGGCUGAAUGGGGCCCCUCUCUGGCUGUCUGAUCCUGUUUUGUACAGGAGGCACCCUCUUAAGUGCUGCAGCCCUCAUUGAGCUUACUGUGCUGACUCCGGCAGCCUGUGGGCUCUGAUGCACUUUUUACAUCCGUUUCUCCAUUUUUUUGGGAGCUUCCUAACAUGCAGGGUAAGGCUUCCUUGCUUUUACUUUUGCCUCUGGGUCUGGACCUCUAGGGGCUCAAGAAAUCCCUGCCAACAAGAGCUUGAGUUUUCAGCCCGUUGCCAGGCCUGUAAUCAGGGAACAGGACCCAUUUCCUCCUGGGACUUCUGGGCCAGCAUCCCAGGCCUCAGGUGCCUCCUUCCACCAAAGGAGGUGCAGGAAAAACAGGGCAUGCAGAGGGUGUGGUCUGUGUGGGCUUCCCCCAGCUCAGCAUAUAUAUGGGUGCGUGGGUGUGAAUGGCAAUACGUGCAGCUGCGCUGUCUGGGAGGAGCAGCCCAGCACCCACACAAGCACACGCCUGUGACGUCACCCAUGCUAGCCCUGCUCAGGCCUAUUUCUGUGAACAUGCAUGCUUCAGCAUGCCCUGGCCUACACUGUACCUGUGCCCAUGCCCAGAGUCUGGGGAGAGUCCCAGCCCAACUGCCCCUCGGGACCUGUGGGUUUGGCCUCACAGCUGUUUAUUAAAUGACCACUUAGAACAGUGGUUGACAUAUAGUAAACACUAUGGAACUGCUUUAUCCACAUUGUCUCAUUUCUUCCUCAUUACAGCCCUAUAAGUGCUCUUAU